AGUCAUUAAAGAACAGCAGCGCCUGGCACGUUCUUGGAGGACCCCGGGCGCAGAGGAGGAAAGGGAGCAGGCGCAGGGGGACUGGAAAGGCAGCAUGCGCUCGCCAGGAGCAACCUCGGCGCCCAGGGUCUGAGGCUGCAGCCCCAGUUCGCCAUUGUGAGCCGCCGCCGGGGGAGUCCGCUAGCGCAGCCGUGCCCCCGAGUCCCCGUCCGCGCAGCGAUGGGGCACCUGCCCACGGGGAUACACGGCGCCCGCCGCCUCCUGCCUCUGCUCUGGCUCUUUGUGCUGUUCAAGAAUGCUACAGCUUUCCAUGUAACUGUCCAAGAUGAUAAUAACAUCGUUGUCUCAUUAGAAGCUUCAGACGUCAUCAGUCCAGCAUCUGUGUAUGUUGUGAAGAUAACUGGUGAAUCCAAAAAUUAUUUCUUCGAAUUUGAGGAAUUCAACAGCACUUUGCCUCCUCCUGUUAUUUUCAAGGCCAGUUAUCAUGGCCUUUAUUAUAUAAUCACUCUGGUAGUGGUAAAUGGAAAUGUGGUGACCAAGCCAUCCAGAUCAAUCACUGUGUUAACAAAACCUCUACCUGUAACCAGUGUUUCCAUAUAUGACUAUAAACCUUCUCCUGAAACAGGAGUCCUGUUUGAAAUACAUUAUCCAGAAAAAUAUAACGUUUUCACAAGAGUGAACAUUAGCUACUGGGAAGGUAAAGACUUCCGGACAAUGCUAUAUAAAGAUUUCUUUAAGGGAAAAACAGUAUUUAAUCACUGGCUGCCAGGAAUGUGUUAUAGUAAUAUCACCUUUCAGCUGGUAUCUGAGGCAACUUUUAAUAAAAGUACCCUUGUUGAGUACAGUGGUGUCAGUCACGAACCCAAACAGCACAGAACUGCCCCUUAUCCACCUCAAAAUAUUUCCGUUCGUAUCGUAAACUUGAACAAAAACAACUGGGAAGAACAGAGUGGCAAUUUCCCAGAAGAAUCCUUCAUGAGAUCACAAGAUACAAUAGGAAAAGAAAAACUCUUCCAUUUUACAGAAGAAACCCCUGAAAUUCCCUCGGGCAACAUUUCUUCCGGUUGGCCUGAUUUUAAUAGCAGUGACUAUGAAACUACGUCUCAGCCAUAUUGGUGGGACAGUGCAUCUGCAGCUCCUGAAAGUGAAGAUGAAUUUGUCAGCGUACUUCCCAUGGAAUACGAAAAUAACAGUACACUCAGUGAGACAGAGAAGUCAACAUCAGGCUCUUUCUCCUUUUUCCCUGUGCAAAUGAUAUUGACCUGGUUACCACCCAAACCACCCACUGCUUUUGAUGGGUUCCAUAUCCAUAUUGAACGAGAAGAGAACUUUACUGAAUAUUUGAUGGUGGAUGAAGAAGCACAUGAAUUUGUUGCAGAACUGAAGGAACCUGGGAAAUAUAAGUUAUCUGUGACAACCUUUAGUUCCUCAGGAUCUUGUGAAACUCGAAAAAGUCAGUCAGCAAAAUCACUCAGCUUUUAUAUCAGUCCUUCAGGAGAGUGGAUUGAAGAACUGACCGAGAAGCCGCAGCACGUGAGUGUCCACGUUUUAAGCUCAACCACUGCCUUGAUGUCCUGGACAUCUUCCCAAGAGAACUACAACAGCACCAUUGUGUCUGUGGUGUCGCUGACCUGCCAGAAACAAAAGGAGAGCCAGAGGCUUGAAAAGCAGUACUGCACUCAGGUGAACUCAAGCAAACCUAUUAUUGAAAAUCUGGUUCCUGGUGCCCAGUACCAGGUUGUAAUAUACCUAAGGAAAGGCCCUUUGAUUGGACCACCUUCAGAUCCUGUGACAUUUGCUAUUGUUCCCACAGGAAUAAAGGAUUUAAUGCUCUAUCCUUUGGGUCCUACGGCCGUGGUUCUGAGCUGGACCAGACCUUAUUUAGGCGUGUUCAGAAAAUACGUGGUUGAAAUGUUUUAUUUCAACCCUGCUACAAUGACAUCAGAGUGGACCACCUACUAUGAAAUAGCAGCAACUGUUUCCUUAACUGCAUCCGUGAGAAUAGCUAAUCUGCUGCCAGCAUGGUACUACAACUUCCGGGUUACCAUGGUGACGUGGGGAGAUCCAGAAUUGAGCUGCUGUGACAGCUCUACCAUCAGCUUCAUAACAGCCCCAGUGGCUCCGGAAAUCACUUCUGUGGAAUAUUUCAACAGUCUGUUAUAUAUCAGUUGGACAUAUGGGGAUGAUACAACGGACUUGUCCCAUUCUAGAAUGCUUCACUGGAUGGUGGUUGCAGAAGGAAAAAAGAAAAUUAAAAAGAGUGUAACACGCAAUGUCAUGACUGCAAUUCUCAGCUUGCCUCCAGGCGACAUCUAUAACCUCUCAGUAACUGCUUGUACUGAAAGAGGAAGUAAUACCUCCAUGCUCCGCCUUGUCAAGCUAGAACCAGCUCCACCCAAAUCACUCUUCGCAGUGAACAAAACCCAGACUUCAGUGACUUUGCUGUGGGUGGAAGAGGGAGUAGCUGAUUUCUUUGAAGUUUUCUGUCAACAAGUUGGCUCCAGUCAGAAAACCAAACUUCAGGAACCAGUUGCUGUUUCUUCCCAUGUCGUGACCAUCUCCAGCCUUCUUCCUGCCACUGCCUACAAUUGUAGUGUCACCAGCUUUAGCCAUGACAGCCCCAGUGUCCCUACGUUCAUAGCCGUCUCAACAAUGGUUACAGAGAUGAAUCCCAAUGUGGUAGUGAUCUCCGUGCUGGCCAUCCUUAGCACACUUUUAAUUGGACUGUUGCUUGUUACCCUCAUUAUUCUUAGGAAAAAGCAUCUGCAGAUGGCUAGGGAGUGUGGAGCUGGUACAUUUGUCAAUUUUGCAUCCUUAGAGAGGGAUGGAAAGCUUCCAUACAACUGGAGUAAAAAUGGUUUAAAGAAGAGGAAACUGACAAACCCGGUUCAACUGGAUGACUUUGAUGCCUAUAUUAAGGAUAUGGCCAAAGACUCUGACUAUAAAUUUUCUCUUCAGUUUGAGCCAAGGACAGCUUUAGUCUGCAAAAAGCAUCAGUGGUCCUGGUGUGGAGACACUAAUGGGGAAUUUGAGGAUGAGAAGAAUCUUAUACAUUACCAAAUACAAAGACCGCUAACUACCACCUGUGUCCUGAAAAAUUCCACACAGAGCCUGCUCACUUAUCCAUUGUAUCCAGGUGCAUAGGAUAUUAUAGAUGCUACACCAAAUGCUAUACUCAAAGAAAUUCAAUUUGAAUUGGAAAUGAAUGAGGAGGAUGGCAUUUCAGAAAGUAUAUCAAGGAAAGGAGGACUUUUUUUCUAAGCAAACAUGAGGCAAAACUCUGAAAAAAUAAAUAGCUAGAUGAUUCUAACGAUGAUAGAAAUUAUGGUAUAGCUACACUUUUACCUUAUUAAAGCCACAUUUUCUUAAUUCCUUCAAGAUGGCAUGCCCUUGGUGGCACAGCUGGAUCAUAACCUCUGCUGGCAACUCACAGUUUAUGUCUUGAAACCCAAGCAUAACUAUUACUGUUUCUGAAUUGCAUGAAAAAAAAUUCAACAAGUCAUUUUCCAGUAAACAUAUUCUUUUAGUUGUGAGUGACAAAAACAUAGCUCAAACUUGUUUAAACUAAAGGAAAGGGGGUUUAUUCAAAGGAUACUAAGGUAUCUCAUACAAUCAAAGAAAAGGUUGAGUAGCUAGACUACGUGCAGGGAAGCAGCACAGUUUCAGGGAUGACUGGAGCCAGGGGCCCCUCUAUUUCUCAUUUCUGCUUCUCUCUCUGUUUUGGUUUCACUUUGUUUCACUGAACAAAGAGAAACAAAGAGAAACGCAGCCAGAGAGGGCAGAUGUUUGUGUUCAGUGAAACAACAAACAACCUCUUUUUCUGUCACUUUUGUUUUGUUUUGUUUUGUUUUUUGAGACAGUCUCACUCUGUUGCCCAGGCUAGAGAGCAGUGGCGCGAUCUUGGCUCACUGCAACCUCCGCCUCCCAGGUUCAAGUGAUUCUCCUGCCUCAGCCUCCUGAGUAGCUGGGACUACAGUUGCCCACCACCAUGCCCGGCUAACUUUUGUAUUUUUAGUAGAGACAGGGUUUCACCAUAUUGACUAGUCUGGUCUCGAACUCCUUACCUUGUGAUCUAGCUGCCUCAGCCUCCCAAAGUGCUGGGAUUACAGCCGUGAGCCACGAUGCCCAGCCCAACCUCUUUUUCAUAGUGAAAAGCAGCCAACAACAACCCUUGAGCACCACAGCCUUUUGUUUCCAUGGUUUCCAAAGGGAAUUACUGUCUGUCUUUCUUGUUUGUAGUUUGAAAAUUAACAGGGGAGGAUUUUGAUGGACGAGCCUGUGUCAUGGUGCCCAUUCAAACCAAUCACAGCCAGAGAGGGCAGAUGCACAGAAUCUCUAAAUGGAACCAUGUGGGCUCAAGUAGCAAAACCUAAGAAGGGCAUUAUCUCCCAAUAAAGAGAGGGUAUUGGGAGAACCAAACCAUAAGCGAUUAGCAUGCUAUCUUUAGAUAUCACAAAAAUAUGAAAAGCAGAAUUAUAAAUUUUAUGUGCUAAAUGUUCAAUUUAUAAUAUGCUGAGGGCUUUUAUUCAUUCAAUGGAUAAAUGAAUACAUUUAGCCUGACUUCAUAGGAUUUAUAAGAAAUGUGCUAAACUAGGAAUCUAAAAUCCUGAAUCCUCACUACAGUGUUGCUACUAAUUAACAUUCUAAAAAAUAUGUUUUUUUCUUAACCAAUUGAUAUAUAAUGAGUUUGGGGUGGGCUUGGGGGCGGAUGAUGUAUUAGCUACAGAUUUUUUAUGUAGUGAACAUGCUCAUGUAUAAGUUUCAAUUUAUCCAACUACUUUGUUGGAAUAAUUCUUAUGGAUUGAAACUGCCCAGGCAAAGUAUAUACAAAAUCUGCAUUUUGAGUAAAUUUCCCAUAAGUGGAGUAAGUUUUCCCAGUGUUCCUAAAACUAUACAAACAGUAUAGUAUAGUAUAUACUUCCUAAAACUAUACAAAGAGUAGAUAUCAACAUUUGUAAUCAUUGAUAAUGUAAUAUUACAAAGAAAUUGCUUUCUCAUCUGUUAACGUUAAGCUACAUCAUCUUCAUAUAGCACUAUUAGUCAUUUGUGUUAUUUCAUUUUCCUCUGUUUCUUUUAUUUUCAUGUACCUUAUAAUCUUCAUCAUUUUGUUACUGAUUUCUAACAGCUGAUUUAUGAUUAAAGAGGUUAACAUUUUGUGAAGGGCUGAAAAUGAAAUACCAUUUUUUUCUCAUUUUUUUACAUUGGGGUUUUAUUUGGAGUUUGUACAGAAGUUGUGUAUUUAAAAAAUAAUCAUGUUCUGCUUUUUUUUAAGUACAUUUUCUCAUCACCUUAGUUUCUUUAUGUAUAAAAUGGGUGAGUUGAACUAGAUCAAUGGUUCUCAACUGGACAAGUACCAGUCAGCCCCCAGAUGAAAUUUGAAAAUGUGUGGGAGUGUUUUUGGUUGUUAUAAUAGCUUAGGAGGAGGAUGCUAACAGUAUUUUAUGGAAGAGGGACGAGGCGUUAAAUGCUCUUCAAUGAGUGGGACAUUCCCGCACAAUAGAGAAUUGUCCUAGGCCGAAAGUGUUUGAUUGAGAAAUAUGGGUUAAAUAUGGGAUGAGGCUACAAUCAAGCUUUAUAACCCAUGUGUAUUAGUCAUGGGUUCUCCAGAGAAACCAAUGGGAUGUUUAUAUAGAACAAAUAUGAUGUAUAUAUAGAGAGAUCUAUUUUAAGGUAUUGGCUUUUGAGGUUAUGGAGGCUGACAAGUCUGAAACCUGAAGGGCAGGCUGGCAGGCUGGAGAUCCAAGGAAAAGUUGAGUUUGCAGUUUUGAGUUUGAAGGCAAUGGGGAGGCAGAAUUCCUCCCUCCUUGUAGGACCUGUCUCUUCUCAUCAGGCCUUCAAACUGACUGGAUGAGGCCCAGCCACAUUACGUAGCAUAAUCAGCCUUCCUCAAACUCUACUUACGUAAAUGUUAAUCACAUAUGAGAAAAACACCUUCACAGCAGCAGACUGGUGUUUGGCCAAGCAACUGGACACUAUAGCCUAGUCAAGUUGACGUCUAAAAUUAACCAUUACACCACGAUUUUAAAGUCUUUAAUAUUGUUAUUUAUUCUGAUGCUCUCUUCAUACAUUUCUAUUCUUAGAACAUUAUUGGUCAUAUAUGUAAUUAAUUGGGUGGUAAGUCCUGACAUUAUUUACAUAUUCUGGUAGGAAAAUACAACUUACUCUCUAGGGCUCUGUUUUAAGUCACAGGCUUAGACUGUAUGUUUUGGACUAACAUUUGCUCAAGCAGUGGCCCGCUGGUCCAAUUUACUUCCUUCUUCAUUUGACAGACUUCAGAUAUUACCAGUCCUCAGUCCCAUUCUGCCCCCUACAUCCUCAGGGUCAGCGUCAGGGUUUCCUCAUCAAUUUUCAUAGAAGUAGUGUGCUCCCAUGCCUGAUUUCAGGAUGUAUGCUGGACCUUUCACAUGGCAGCCCUCACAUUUUUUUGAAAUACAUUGAUAGUUAAUUGAGACUUAAGGAAAAAAAUGUUCCUAACUCUAAUGAGAAUUCAAGAGGGUAUGAGAUGGCCAAAUCACCUUGGUCUAGAUAAUUCCAGCAGCUGAACUUGUACUUGUUCUGUUUAUAUUAAUGCCUAGUAUUUGUAUUCAUUUUGAUACUGACAUUGAAAUAUCACAUUCACAUUGAGAAAUCACAUCAUUUAUAAGCAUUUUGCAGAUUGAAACUAAUGUCUGGAUUUAUAGAUACUACCAAUACAGCCAUAAGUCAUACAUGAAGCUAUAUGAGUUACUAAUUUGUGUUUACUGAAUAAAUUUCUUUUUUACUCUGAAUCUGAUUUUAAAUCUGCUAGAAAGAUUGAUUAUCCUUCUGAUAAAAAUAUACACCGUUCCUUUAAAAGUCUUGGGACCCAGGGAUUAAAAUAGGUUCCUCAUUUUUUACAUUUCACAUGGGAAAGAUUUUGAAGAACCAGACUUUAUAGCUGAAAUGUGAGAGCCCAGAAGACAUAUCACAUAUUGCUCAUUCUGCUAUUAAUGUCUGUGCUUAGUGUUUGAUCAGGAUACUAGUAAAGGCCCUCACCAUCUCUGUUCAGACAUGUGGCUGCAAAGAUCAAAACAAAACUACAGAACUGGCCAUGCAGUUCACAAGAGGUGACCUUUGAUUUCUGGUAGUAGCUUUUACUUGCUAUAGAUGGAACCUCUUCUGUCAACACCACUGGCACUUUCUUUCUCCUCACUUUUUCCACCCCUUAUGGACACGUAAUCUAGUAAUCUUAGUAUUGUUUGAAUAAACCCCCUUUCCUUUAGUCUAAACUAGUUUGAGCUAUGUUUUUGUCACUCACAACUAAAAUAAUGUGUUUACUGGAAAAUGACUUGUUGGAUUUUUUGUAAUCAUGCGAUUCAGAAACAGUAAUAGUUAUGCUUGGGUUUCAAGACAUAAUGUCCACCCUAUCCCAAAGCAAACACCGAAAGCAAACUCUCACCUGCUGACAUUGUUACAAACCCUAAGACCAGAAUGCAGAUUGUGCUCUCCUCAGAAGAUGAUAUUGCAGGUUAUGGGCUGAAUAUCUGUGGCCCCCCAAAAUUCCUAUGUUUAAUCCCUAACCCCCAAUGCAAUGGUAUUUGGAGAUGGAGCCCUUGCUAAGUAAUUAGGAUUAGAUAAGCUCAUGAGGGUGAGGACUUCGUGGUAGGAUUGUUGCAGGACUUUUCCUUAGUUCAGCUAAAGAUGAGGUCCUUGUCCAUCCCACAGCCAUGAAAAUUUAGGUUCACAGGCAAUUUGGAGGGUGAGUAAAACAGGGUUUUAUUCGGUGAAAAGGAAGAAAAGGGAGAAACAGGGACUCUCACUAGGCUGGAGUCCCUGCUAGAGCACUUCCCACUGGCAGCUUGAAUCUCAGGUUCCACACAGGAAGAGGAGAGGCCAGGUUCCUUCCCCACUGCAAACAUGGUGAACUUCCCGAGGCUCCACCUCUGUGAGCAGGCUAGUUGGAAUUUCUCCAAGGACCCCCUCCCACCUGACUGUCUCAGGAUCAGCCAAGAUAAGAUGCCUAAGAAUGAAAUCUACCUUGUUGCCAUCUUGAUCUUGGACUUCCCAGCCUCCAGAACUGUGAGACAUAAAUCUCUACUGUUUAAACUAUCACUCUAUGGUGUUUUGUUAUGGCAGCCCAAGCCAACUAAUGUAAUGUAUAUGCUUGUGCUUUGCUUUCCAAGACCUGUAUGCUUCAAACACAGCCAACAAAACGUAGCCUGCUACUGGGUUUGGGUGACCGUAUUAGUUCCUAUGGCUGCCAUAACAAAUUACCACAAUUGUCGUGGUUUAAAACAACAGAAACUUAUUCUCACAAUUGCAGAGCCAGAAUUCCAAAAUCAAGGUGUCAGCAGGGCCACACUCCCCCUGAAGACUCUAGGGAAGAAUUUUUCUUUGCCUCUUUCAGCUUCUGUUGGCCACAGCAAUUCCUUGGCUUGCAGCUGCAUAACUCUGAUCUGUCUCCAUCUUUACAUGCCUUUUCCUCUUCUCCAGGAUGAUCUCAUCUCAUGUUCUCUAACUUAAUUACAACUGCAAAGACACUUUCUCCAAAUUAGAUCACACUCACAGGUUCUGGGGGUUAGGAGGUAGACGUAUCUUUUUGGGGAUCACCAUUCAACCCACUACAGAUGACUGUAUAGCCUAGAAGAAAAGGGUGAUAAAUUAUAUUUAGAAACAAAACUGACAAAAGAAAAUUCAGAAAUGAUUUAUGUGGGUUUCAGGUCCAUCACUCCAUAGUUUGUCUUCAUAAAGAUUUAAGCCAGUGGAAUUUCCAUAUGGUUGGAAAGAAAAUAACUUCAAAGCUGCUGAACUGGAAACUUAAUAUUUUAUUUUCCACUUAGUGACAGGCUAAAUUACAAAGGCUUCAAAGCAUACUGUGUUUACAUGCAGUUCCCACUUUGCUGCAAUUCAACUUUGGCAACUUCCACUUACAGUGUUCAGCCAAUUAAACCUCUCUUAUCAACUUAGAGUAUUUACAGCAGGAAGGCAACACACAAUUAAAGUUCUGUCAGUUAGUCAGCUUCCACAAUUAAAGUUCUGUCAGUUAGUCAGCUUCCACAUGUGCUCAAACGCUCAGCCUCAAUCUGUUUCCACCAUUCCUUUUGUAUCUGAGGCCUUUUCCCAUGGCUUAUCAGUCUGUCCCCAAAGCAAGAGAAUUGGGGGAAGAGUUGUUGGUCUGCUGGCAUAAAUGGCAGAGGAGGAAGAAAUUAUGGAGCCAGGCAAAGCAAAACAAAGAAUCAUCACAAAAGUAUUUUACAAUGAUCAUCAAUAGUGCUGUAUUAGUAUUUGUUGAGUUAAAUUAUUCCAUUUGAUAAUCACUAUAAAAAAGGAAGGUGUGGAGAAAUUACUAGCCUUAUCUUACAGGUAAUUAAAGCAAAGUUUAAAAGAGUUUAACUACCCUUCCAAGAACAUACAGUUUAUAAGUGGCAUGUCAGAAUAUGUGAGAUAUUUUGAAAAAAUAUCUAUGCAGGCAUUUUCUAAAGGAGGUAGAUUUCUGAAAUAAUUUAAGCAAUGGAAGCAUCAUUUAAAUAAACUUAUAACUACCAAAAGGAACUAACCUAAACAUCACACUGAUUUAGUUGAAAUUUACUAAAAAUAAGUUGCUUCUUACAAGAAAAAUAGAGUCAACCUUUGAAUACCCUUUAAAAUGGAACACUCAGUUAUAAAAUAACAAUGGGAAGCAUCUGCCUAAAUAUAUUUGGCAAGUAAGUGCCUGAGAUGGAAAAAACCAAUUUUGUGAGUUGAAAAUCAAAUGUAACAUAGUUUGUAUAUAAAACUGACAUCAACUUAGUCCAAAGAACUUCAGAUAUUGUCAUCUUGAAAAGCCAAAAGAGAUGAGGAAUCAAAGGAAGAGAGAAAUCUGGGCAAUUUUUGUUGGUUCAUCCAUGUUGGCUACAGUCAGGCAACCCAAUGCCAUUAAGCGCAAGGUAAUUUGCCACCAAGGAUCUUCUAGUUAAAAGCAUCAGAAGACCCAAUAACUUGAUUAAUAAAGCAUGUGCUUUGCAAAGAGCACUUGAAUAAAGACACAAAGGGCAUGAAACAGAUAUCCCUAUUCAAUCCUAGAACGUGGUCAAGUGGCUCCAAUUCUCUUCAACAGUGUUAAAAGACCCUCCGAAAUUCUUCUCCUAGGGAAGUAUUCCUCCAGCUUUGAUUCCUUGAAGUAAUAAUUGGGAGGAAUUAUGAAGAGUAAAACUUGUGCUCAAUAUUAACAUUCUAUAAAUGUAAAUAAAAUUUAUAACAAGUGAUUUUUGCCUCGCUUAGUAGUCUUAUAGAAAGAUGCACACUAUGUGGGUAAUCCCACUUAUACACAGUUAUGUACACUGUUUACUAACAUUCCUCUAACAUUUGUAUAGGAAUAUAACUAGAUCCACUGCAUUGGUUGCACAUUGUACAACUCCAGUGAACACCGUUCAUAUAGACCACAAUGUGAAUGAUGCCUCCAAGAAAUACAGGUGGCCUGACCGUAAUCCCCGUUUCCUGUAAGACACAUGGCAUAGCAACUUAGAAAUCCCCCUUUCCCCAUAACAUACCCUUUUUGAAGUGUGACAGUUAUUUAUAUAAAAAUUUCCCAUCAGUUCACCUUCUGAAAUGAGGUUUAUAAGAGUACCAAUAUACGCAGGCAGACAUUUGGAUGUUCUUAUUCUCACUGAAGGAUUUUCCCCAACAACUACAGAUCCAUCUUUAUGUUUGAGGUUUCAUUACCAGAUAUUUAGUGACUGUUAAUCCCAUACUUUGUAACAUGGAGAUUGUUCCCUACUCAUUCCUCACUAUUUUUUACUACUUUCUCUAAGGCUCAUUGCCUACAAGAAAAAAAAAGCCUAGAUUUCUUCAGAGAAUAGGAAAUAUUUAUACAAAUUGCAUAAACUUAAGUUACUCUAUUCCUCCAAAAAUCUGAAAUGCAUUUUUAUUUUCAAAUAUUUCAUACCCUGAGUGUUAUACAUAUAGUUCUUACUUCUCCAAAUGACCACUAAGUUAUCCAAGGUAUUUAUGUGUUGUAUUAGAUAGCUAUUACCACAAUAAUGCUGUAUAAGAAACAACCUCAAAAUCUCUACAAUAACAUUUACUUUUCUCACUCAUGGGUCUGUGGAACAGCUGGGGCAGUUCUGCUUCAGGCUGUGGGUCAGAGUCAGGUCUGCCCUAUGUGCCUCCUCAUUCUCGGACUAGCAGCUUCCCUGGGCAUGUCUUUUUCAGGGUAGAUGGCAGGCACACAAGAGGGCAAACCAAACAAGCAAGUGCAUUGAAAGCUUCUGAGUGGACUUGAUUUCUAUCUAAGAUCAUUGGCCAAAGCAAGUUGAUGAUAGUGGGGUGGAGUACCUUCCACCUCUAAAGGGAGCUACUGCAAUGUCAUAUAGCAAAGGGCUUGUGAGCAAUAAACCAGUUGAACAAUAAUCCAAUUCACACCACGUAUGGAACUCUCAAAUCCAUUCUCUGUC